GCUGGAGCCCGGGGCCGCGGAGCCGGGCCGGGGCAGCGCCGUCUCCGCCUCGGGGCCGCCGGGGGCGCCCUGCUGAGCGCUACCCACGUGCGUCCGCGCCACCUCGCGGGCGACCCCGCGGCCAAGGCCCCCGGCGGAGCGGCUCCCGGGCGCCCCGAACUAGCCCCCAACUUUGGGCGAAGUUUGCCUGCGCCUCUCCCCGCCCCCACGCGGCGCGCCGGGGCCGCGGACGGCAGCGGCCCCCGGGGAUGCGCCUUCCCGGGGUACCCCUGGCGCGCCCUGCGCUGCUGCUGCUGCUGCCGCUGCUCGCGCCGCUGCUGGGAACGGGUGCGCCGGCCGAGCUGCGGGUCCGCGUGCGGCUGCCGGACGGCCAGGUGACCGAGGAGAGCCUGCAGGCGGACAGCGACGCGGACAGCAUCAGCCUCGAGCUGCGCAAGCCCGACGGCACCCUCGUCUCCUUCACCGCCGACUUCAAGAAGGAUGUGAAGGUCUUCCGGGCCCUGAUCCUGGGGGAGCUGGAGAAGGGGCAGAGUCAGUUCCAGGCCCUCUGCUUUGUCACCCAGCUGCAGCACAAUGAGAUCAUCCCCAGUGAGGCCAUGGCCAAGCUCCGGCAGAAAAAUCCCCGGGCAGUGCGGCAGGCGGAGGAGGUUCGGGGUCUGGAGCAUCUGCACAUGGAUGUCGCUGUCAACUUCAGCCAGGGGGCCCUGCUGAGCCCCCAUCUCCACAACGUGUGUGCCGAGGCCGUGGAUGCCAUCUACACCCGCCAGGAGGAUGUCCGGUUCUGGCUGGAGCAAGGUGUGGACAGUUCUGUGUUCGAGGCUCUGCCCAAGGCCUCAGAGCAGGCGGAGCUGCCUCGCUGCAGGCAGGUGGGGGACCACGGGAAGCCCUGCGUCUGCCGCUAUGGCCUGAGCCUGGCCUGGUACCCCUGCAUGCUCAAGUACUGCCACAGCCGCGACCGGCCCACGCCCUACAAGUGUGGCAUCCGCAGCUGCCAGAAGAGCUACAGCUUCGACUUCUACGUGCCCCAGAGGCAGCUGUGUCUCUGGGAUGAGGAUCCCUACCCAGGCUAGGGUGGGAGCAACCUGGCGGGUGGCUGCUCUGGGCCCACUGCUCUUCACCAGCCACUAGAGGGGGUGGCAACCCCCACCUGAGGCCUUAUUUCCCUCCCUCCCCACUCCCCUGGCCCUAGAGCCUGGGCCCCUCUGGCCCCAUCUCACAUGACUGUGAAGGGGGUGUGGCAUGGCAGGGGGUCUCAUGAAGGCACCCCCAUUCCCACCCUGUGCCUUCCUUGCGGGCAGAGAGGGAGAGAAGGGCUCCCCAGAUCUACACCCCUCCCUCCUGCAUCUCCCCUGGAGUGUUCACUUGCAAGCUGCCAAAACAUGAUGGCCUCUGGUUGUUCUGUUGAACUCCUUGAACGUUUAGACCCUAAAAGGAGUCUAUACCUGGACACCCACCUCCCCAGACACAACUCCCUUCCCCAUGCACACAUCUGGAAGGAGCUGGCCCCUCAGUCCCUUCCUACUCCCCAACAAGGGGCUCACUAUCCCCAAAGAAGGAGCUGUUGGGGACCCACGACGCAGCCCCUGUACUGGAUUACAGCAUAUUCUCAUCUCUGGCCCCGAGGCUGCCUGUGGGGCGAGUGGAGACCUCCCAUCACUGAGACAGAUCACAGACCACGAGUGCCUUUCCCGGACCUGGACGUUGCCUCCAGAGCAGGCACCAGCUCUUUCCCUCUCUACACAGAAAUAUUUUUGUAAGGUUCUGGGGCAGGGAGGGAGCAUGAAGUACGAGGAAAACUUGAAUUCCAGAUUUUUAGUGCAAAGUAUUUAUCAUUUCUACCAGAAAUAAACGUUUUAAGUUUUUACUUGACUAAUGAGACCCAGAGUUUGGAGAAAACUUUUGGCCAAUGCUGCCACCUGAUGUCAGAAAGUGUCCCCACACCCUAGCAGUGGCCUAUCUUGGAACAAGAACUUCGAAAGCACCUACUGUGUGCUCAGCCAUUUGAGGAAGGAAGGAGGAGAAGGAAGAUGUUACUAGGGAAGGAUGAGAUAAAACUUCUGCACCCAAGACAAUGAGACAGACAUAGCUGCAACCGUAGUAAGCCAGUCAGAAAUAGCCAGCGCGAAGGCAAGAGAUGGGGUGGAGAUUGGAACCCCGCUUCAGAUCUGGGCUCGGCUACUUACCUGCUGUGCAGCCAUGGGUCAAGUUGCUUGACCUCUCUGUGCCUCCACUCCCUUAGCUAUAAAAUGAGCUUACUUAAGA